GAGAGGCUCGGCCAGGCGGGAGCUGCGCUCGGGGCGGCCGCUGCACCUGCCCGGGACCCCGCCGGCCGCUCCCCGCGCCCACCCCUUCCGCCCUUCGCCCCCCCCUUCCCCCCAGCCCCGGUCUCCCGGGCGCGGCGUGAGAGCAGAGCCCGGCCCGGAGGAGCCGCCCCUUCCCCGCCCGCCCGCCCGGCGCCUGGAGAGGAGCGCGCUGAGGAUCGGGACGCCUGCGGCCGCCGCCACCGCCCAGGCCCGUCGCGCCCCGGCCGGGAUGGACCCACACGCCCGAUGAGCCCCGCGCCGGCGGCUGCGAGCGCCGAGCCUCCCCCUGCUGCGGCCCCAGCCGCCCCCCGCGCGCCCGGCUCCGCGGACCAGGACCCCUGGGCUCCCCGGCUGAGGGCGCGGCCGCUCCGGAGAGGCCGAGCGGGGACGGGCCCGAGAUGGCGCGGGGACCCAGCGCUCCGGCGGCGGGCGCCCUGCACGCGGCCCGGGCCCGGGGACAGCCCCGGAGCUGGUAGCCGCCCGGCACCGAUGGACCUUGACCCGCGAGGCGGCGCCGCGCUCGUGCCCAGCUGCAGCUAGAGGGGCGCGCGGGCAGAACGCGCUCCAGGCCCGGGCCGGCCCGCGCGGCCAUGAAGAUGAUGCUGGUGCGCCGGUUCCGCGUGCUCAUCCUGAUGGUGUUCCUGGUGGCCUGCGCGCUGCACAUCGCCCUGGACCUGCUGCCCAGGCUGGAGCGACGCGGCGCGCGGCCCUCGGGGGAGCCCGGCUGUUCGUGCGCGCAGCCCGCCGCCGAGGUGGCCGCGCCCGGCUGGGCCCAGGUUCGGGGCCGCCCCGGGGAGCCCCCGGCCGCCUCCUCCGCCGCCGGCGACGCGGGCUGGCCCAACAAGCACACGCUCCGCAUCCUGCAGGACUUCAGCUCCGACCCCUCCUCCAACCUCUCGUCCCACUCGCUGGAGAAACUGCCGCCCGCGGCCGAGCCGGCCGAGCGCGCCUUGCGGGGGCGGGAUCCCGGCGCCCUAAGACCCCACGACCCCGCGCACCGGCCGCUGCUGCGAGACCCCGGCCCGCGUCGGUCCGAGUCGCCCCCCGGCCCCGGCGGAGACGCCUCCCUCCUGGCCAGGCUGUUCGAGCACCCGCUUUACCGGGUGGCGGUUCCGCCGCUCACGGAGGAGGACGUCCUGUUCAAUGUGAACAGCGACACCAGGCUCAGCCCCAAAGCGGCGGAGAACCCGGACUGGCCGCAUGCGGGUGCUGAAGGUGCAGAAUUCCUCUCCCCCGGGGAGGCGGCCGUGGACUCCUAUCCCAACUGGCUCAAGUUCCACAUUGGUAUCAACCGGUACGAGCUGUACUCCAGACACAACCCGGCCAUCGAGGCCCUGCUGCACGACCUCAGCUCCCAGAGGAUCACCAGCGUGGAUUUUACUGGCACCUCCUGCAUGUCAGACCCCCUUUCUGGGUGGUGGGGAGUUGAGGAUGAGUUCAGCCUCAACGAGAUCUGCUGCCUCUGUGGACCUGACAGCCCCAGGAAGAGACACACACGCACAGUGCCCGAUCCUGAGGAGGAACGAGCACUUCAGAGCCGUGCACGCCAGCCAGGCCGUGUGGAGAGGAGGGGGCUCCACUGGGAGGGGCUGAGGACCUUCCACAGGGUCUGUCGGGCAGCUUACCUUCCAGGUGGGUCCGUCUUGGCAGGGAGAGGAAUGAGAGAGCCGUGCACACCAGCCAGGGCGUUCGGGAGGAGCAGCACGCAAGUUAGAAAGUCCCCAGUGCCGCUGUCCGUAUGAGCUUCUCUCCAGCUCAUUUUCCCCAUCUGUCCAGUGGGAUCUCGCUGCGUGGGACCAAUGCAAGGAUAGGAUGAGAUGUGCAUGUGAGCAAGCUUGUUAAAUAUUAACUAGUACUUUGUGCGUGGCCUUCCACAACAGUCCCCUCGUGUGCACAGGCAGGGUCUGAGCAGAGGGAGGGCUUUGUGGAUUCCAAAGGCCACCAGGCCCUUGGCAGGCAACUGCAGCUCGCCACCUCCCUCACCGACCGGUCAGCUUUCCAACACCAACACUGAAGAGGUGUGGGAGUUCUGUGCCAGGAGCUCCCAGAGCAGCUUCAGGGAGAGUGUGGGGCCCCCUGGGACCUGGGGCAUCUUUGCCCACCUUAGGAGUGCUUUGUCCAUCUGGACAAGCUAGGCUUGGCUCACUGCCACCCCUCUUUGGUCCAGCUGUCCCGGGGCAGUGGUGCCCAGGCUGCCUGACAUUGCAGGGGUGUGGACAGAGCCCUUGCCAGGGAAUCCCUACCCCAGGAUUCUGGUGUGGCCUCCGCCUGGGUGUGUCCUGGUUAAUUCCUGUGCCUACUGAAGGCCUGCCCCAGCUGAUCUCGCUCGCUCGCCUCCUAGACCAUGCUGGCCACAUUGGUUCUCAUCCAGUCUUCUGGGGUGGGGACCCGUCCAAGGACAGGCUGGCUGCUCAGUCAUUCUGCAGGGCCAAGCAGGGCCUGCAAGGACGAUGGGCAGACACAGCCGCAUCACCCAGGCAGGACAGCAGGCUCUGGCCCAGGAGAUCUGGGGGUGAAUCCUGGCUCUGCCAGCCAUUAGCCAGAGUGGAAGUGGGCAAAUGGAUUAACGCCUCCAGCACCUGGUUUCUCACCGAGAACACAGAGAAGGUUAUAAUCUGGACCUGGUAUAAUCUGGACUCUGACUUACAAAUCUGAAUGCCAAGCAAAACCCAUUCACUAGCGAAAACUGACUCAGGCUGAACGUAUUUAGGGGCAAAACCUAAAUUGUCGAGGCUAGUUAAAAGUCCUGAUUUUUCUCUGUUACAUUGAAUAGUCACAUGUUCCUCUGAGGAACAGGAGUGGGUUUAAUUAUGGGGUUCUGCCCUAGACCCGUGUGGGCAUGCCAUGAUCCACACCAUGCACCACGUGUGCCUUUGUCAUCGAAAUACCUGCAGUUCCCAAAUACAUCUGGCCUCACAGGGUUGUUGGGGCUUAAAUGUGCAAAUACGAGUAAAGAGGUGAGAGCGGAGCCUGACAGCGCACCUGCUGGGCAGGGUCUCCAACACUGCAGCAUUUUGGGGGAAGCUCUCCUACUGGGUGGGGUCUUUGUACAGCAGCAGCAUUUCAAGGUGGGCUGAUCCUUCUCAUCUGGGGAAGCCAGGGCUGGGCAGGUGCCUGAGCCUCAUGAGGGUCUCAGUCUAGAUGCUGGGCCCUAUUCUCCCUGCUGCCUUGGGCUUGGAGAUGCUCACAGGUGAGUUCUCAUUUGUGAAGAGGUCUGUCUUCCUGAGGAAGCAGGGGACCCUCACCUGUGAACCAAGUGUGCCAUGGGAGCUGCUCCAUGUCCAGGUCCAGGUCUCCUGGUCUGCAGGGAACGGCACAAGAGGGCUGGCCUAGGCCAGGAGGAUGUGAUCUGUCCUAGAAGGGGGCUGACCUGCUUGCUGACCCCGCUUGCUGCUGCCUGGCUGGCCUGACUCAGCCACGGCUGUUCCGAGGGCCCUUCUGAGUACGAACUUCCAGUUGGAGGAUCUGGGUGAAGACCCAGCUGCUUGAGAUAGCAGCCUCUGGCUAGGCCCUUGGCGUGGCCAAGCCAAUCAGGCAGGUUUAGAGCCUGGUGCCCCUAGACAGGUCCUGCAACCAAGAACAGGGGUAGCCUUCAAAGGCCAGCCCUGCCUUCCAACCACCGCUCCACAGCGAGGGAAACCAAGGCUCUUAGGGCAGGAGGCUUGUCCGAGAUUAGCACCUGCGUGCUCCAGGCUCUGAGUUCUGUCCCCUCAGCUGUCCGGCCCCUGGGUGCUCACUUUAAUCUCAAGUCAUUCAUCUUACUAUUAAACGUGAGCCCAGAAAUAUUGUUGUAAUGGAGAACGAUGCCUGCGAGUCUCCAAAGCCUUCCCUCGGAACGGUUCCAUUAAAUCUCUCCUGCUCAGAACCACCCAAUCCAAUUCAUGGAGCGCCACGUGGUCUACAGCACAGCUGGUUAGGGCCAGCGGAGGUUUAUUUAUAGCUGGGCUCCUGGCUGCCUGGUAACCGGCCAUUGCCACCUUUAAAGAGUCUUGGGAUAUUAUCUACCUCUAUUCAGCUUGAAAUCGGGCAUGCAGUGCCUUGGGCUGGGGCUGGCGAUAAUUAAAUUUCUAUCAUGCACAAUUAUGGAUGCAAAGAAUGAAUGACAUCCCACUGGCAUGUGAGGAUUCGGGCAGCUUCUGGACUGAAAUACAGACUUCAUAAUUGCUCCAUCCAGAUUGGGACAAAGACUGUGGUUGGGAGAACAUGCCUGAACAAAGAAAAAUGACUCUGCAGGACCAAAGUUCUUGACACUGAUUGAUCUGCCAAAAGGGGAAGAAUGAGUCCAGCUAGAAUCCAGGACUAACCAGCGGGUGAGCUUCAAGGAACAAAGGGCUUCCGCUGGGUCAGCCCACGAGAGGGAGCUGCCUGCAGGUACCUGGGAGGGCACAGCCACCGUGUCUGUUCCUUGGGAGCAGGGCUCCUUGGAAGGCAGCGCCAGCUCCAGAAAGGCCACUGUUCCCCCUCCCACCCACCCCAGGUGGCAACUGCCCCUGCAGGUCACGGUCCCAGGGCCUCGCUCGGCCGGCCUAGAGAGAGAAAAGGGAAGAUGCCCAAUUAGCUGGACGCCCAUGGCCCCAGGGCUGGGGGACCUUGGGUUAUCCUGAAAGAAGGACAAUGACCACCUGCAAAGGACGAUUUCAAGUGGAGCCUGGAGGAGGCGGCAAAUAGCUCAGUCCGCACUCAACUCCCUUCCCAGCCGUCUGGUGGAAGGUGAGGAGCAAAAGCUCAUGCUGCUGAGGCCUGGGGCCACCCAGGCACCGGCCUCCCCGUGCUGAGCAGAGACAGCAGCCCCCUAGCUGCAGGAGUGUGCCCCGAUGCGCACCUGCCGACUUUCCUUCUGAUGCAGACAUGGUCCCCACUGGGGCAAGGCUGCAGUUUUCUUUUAAAAAACAGAUCUUUCAAAAUAAAAGGGGCCUUGAAGAAAA